CAUCAAACUCAUUCUCUGUCCAGUUUUGUUCCCUUGCUGGUGAGGAGUUGUGAUCCUGUGGAGGAGAAGAAGUGUGCUGGUUUUUGGAAUGUUCAGCCUUUUUGCACUGGUUUUUCCUCAUCUUCAUGGAUUUAUCUACCUUUGGUUUUUGCUGUUGGUGACCUUCAGAUGGAGGUUUUACGUGGACGUACUUUUUGUUUAUGUUGAUGCUACUGCUUUCUCUUCGUGAGUUUUCCUUCUAACAGUCAAGUCCCUCUUCUGCAUGUCCGCUGGAGUUUGCUGGGGGUCCACUUCAGACCCUGUUUGCCUGGGUGUCACCAGCAGAGGCUGCAGAACAGCAAAGAUUGCUGCCUGCUCCUUCCUCUGGAAGCUUCAUCCCAGAGGAGCUCCUGCCAGAUGCCAGUCAGAGCUCUCCUGUAUGAGGUGUUUGUCAAUCCCUGCUGGGAGAUGUCUCCCCAUCAGGAGGCCCAGGGGUCAGGGACUUGACCCUUGAGGAGGUAGUCUGUCCCUUGGCAGAGCUUGGGCACUGUGCAGGGAGAUCCGCUGCUCUCUUCAGAGCUGGCAGGCAGAAAUGUUUAAGUUUGCUGAAGCUGCACCCACAGCUGCCCCUCCCCCAAGGUUCUCUGUCCCAGGGAUAUGGGAAUUUUAUCUAUAACCCCCUGACUGGGGCUGCUGCCUUUCUUUCAGAGAUGCUGUGUCCAGAGAGGAGGAAUCUAGAGAGGCAGUCUGGCUAUAGUGGUUUGGUAGUGAUGUGGUGGGCUCCACCCAGUCCACACUUCCCAGAGGCUUUGUUUGCACUGUGAGGGGAAAGCCGCCUACUCAAGCCUCAGUAAUGGUGGAUGCCCCUCCCCCCACCAAGCUGGAGCAUCCCAGGUGGACUUCAGACUGCUGUGCUGGCAGCGAGAAUUUCAAGCCAGUGGAUCUUAGCUUGCUGGGCUCCGUGGGUGUGGGAUUUACUGAGCAAGACCACUUGGCUCCCUGGCUUCAGCCCCCAUUCCAGGGAAGUGAACAGUUCUGUCUCGCUGGCGUUCCAGGCACCACCGGGGUAAGAAAAAAAAAAACUUCUGCAACUAGCCCAGUGUCUGCCCAAAGGGCUGCCCAGUUUUGUGCUUGAAACCCAGAGCCCUUGUGGUGUAGGCACCCAAGGGAAUCUCCUCCCUGGUCUGUAGGUUGUGAAGACCAUAGAAAAAUGUAGUAUAUGGGUUAGAGAGCACCAUUCCUCACGGCACAGUCCUUCACGGCUUCCCUUGGCUAGAGGAAGGAGUUCCCUGACCCCUUGCACUUCCUGGGUGAGGCAAUGCCCCACCCUGCUUCUGCUUGCCCUCCAUGGGCUGCAUCCACUGUCUAACAAUCUCAAUGAAAUGAAUCUGGUACCUCAGUUGGAAAGGCAGAAAUCACCUGCCUUCUGCGUUGGUCUCGCUGGGAGCUGCAGACCAGAGCUGUUCCUAUUCAGCUAUCUUGCUCAGGAAUCCUAGAGCAUCUUUAAUACAUCAGUGUGCAUUAUGGCACAACAAAUGAAGAAUUGAGCGUAAGAGUUCUCCCAGACUUAUUUGACAGUAGAAUGGUUUAUUCUACAGAAAGUUUGUUUAACAAUUUGUGGAACUAGUUAGUAUUCUAUAGAAUAAACUUUGUCAUUGCUGUUCUAGUAUCAUGGUAAGGUGCUGGAAACCCUAAUGCCAAUGCUGCAACACACAGCACUGAGGUAAAAGCUGCACAUGUGAGCACAUAUGCAUUCCAGCCAUAUUAUUUUUGACCAGCUACUAGGAUUUUAAAGAUUACUCGAGUUAAUUUUAAAAACCACCUUGGCUCACGCCUGUAAUCCCAGCACUUUGUGAGGCCAAGGUGUGUAGAUCAUGAGGCCAGGAGUUUGAGACCAGCCUGACCAACAUGAUGAAACCCCGUCUCUACUAAAAAUACAAAAAUUAGCUGGGUGUGGUGGCACAUGCCUGUAAUCCCAGCUACUCAGGAGGCUGCGGUAGGAGAAUCGCUUGAACCCGGCAGGCGAAGGUUGCAGUGAGCUGAGAUCAUGCCACUGCAUUCCAGCCUGGGUAACAGAGUUAGACUCCAAAAAAAAAAAAAAAAAAAAAAAACAAAAACACCUCUAAUAUCUGAAAUAUCCUGAGUCAUGGCAUUGAAGAAAGCAAUGGAGUUUGUAUCAAUCUAAGACAGGAUUACAUUUCAAUCGUCCAAGAUUAUUUAUAAGAAAGGACCUAGAUUAGCAUCUUACAAUCAAUUCCAGCAUAGCCUAAAUCUACCUGUCUUUUAUUUAGAACAUAAUGUUACUUGAGCAUUUCCUUAAGUUCCCUAGGUAGUAUUCCACUACAGACGACCAAUAUUAAGGUAUAUUUUCUGGGUUGUAUGGAGUUCACUCACUGGCAAGACCUCUGAGUAAACAGAAUUUAUAAUAACAUUGGUAUUUUCCAUAUUCAUUUGGCAAAGAUCAGCUUCCACACUGAGGUGAUUUUUCAACCAGUGGAUGAGGCAAACAAAAUCUUCUAAUAGCUUUCCAUUACUUAAAAGGUUAAAAACAGAGGAGAGGGGGAUCUUAAGCAUAAUGACAGCUCUUCCUUGUUCUUUUUUAUAUAAAUGAAUGGAUUCUCAAUAACUACACCAAGUGACCCGUCCUAUCAUCAUCCCUCUCUCAUCCUAGAAAUAGAUGAGAACCCAAUCAGCUGAUUUAUGACUCAUUUGGACAGUGAUGGAAAUGGAGAGGAUCGUUCUUUUCAGCAGGCCCCGAACCCACCUCAGAACUAUCUUUAAAGUUGAACCCAUGACUGAGGAAGCACCAAAGCAUUUCCUUAUUUUGGCAGUUUAUUUUUUUUAAAUAAGUAUUCAUCAUCUUACUCCCUUUCCUUCUUUAGAUACACAAUUUUCCCCUCAAAGAUUAAAUUAUCUAUAUUAGUACUUUUCUAUACCCUAAUUAUUUAAAAAAUCCAAGUAAUAUGCUUAUAGGCCCAAUCUCAUUAACAAUAUAUUCUAAGCUAUAAGCUCUCAUUUCAAUAUAAGAGCAAAGGAAAGCAGGGUGUAUAAACUGAAUCUGCAAGGUCCUGAUCACAGUUAGUUAAAUUUACUGUAGACCACUCAAUAGCUUUCCAAACACUGGCCUCCUUAUUUCUCACAUGUUGGGUUCAUCAAUUAAGAUAUAUUUGGGCAAUUAGCAUCAACCACUUUUGUUCUUCCGUAAUUUGCCUGAUCAUAAUUUUGACAAUAUUUAUCUUGUUAAAAAUUUGGUCUAAAUGUCUCUUACAAUGAGCUAAGAAAUGUCAAAUAAUGAUUUGUUCUACCCUGGGGCAAGCCGUAUUCCUAAGCAGAUUCAAUCAGGAGCACCUGCAAAACAUAUAAGUUACCCAGGCUUCCUUGUCUAUAGGGACCGUUUUUGUUCCAGAUUGAACAGAAGUUUUAGGUUUGCUCAAACUCAUUCUUAUUGUAUAUGAAAUACACCCUUCUUAUAAUGGACCCAAUUUAUUUAUUAGUAUAUGCAUUCAUUCAUUCACUUAUUAACUUAUUUUUCUACCUGCAUCUGAUGCAAAACAUCUCACCUUUUUGUACCAGGCAAAACAGAAACGAACAGGCAAAACCUGAACGAACCAAACAAAAACUGAUUUUCUCUUCCGCUUGAGAAAAUGCAACUCUAAUGUCCUCAACAGUUUCUUACUGCCUCCAGGUUGUUAGCGACAUGAGUACAGGGUCUGGAUCUUACCCAUUCAAGAGUGUAUUCUCAGCACCCAAUGCCUGGCAUAUAGUUUAAAUGUUUAUUUGCUACUUGGCUACUGAUUAGAGAACGCAAAAUGAAUAACUCAACAAACUCCUCUAACAAUAGCCUGGCUCUUACAAGUCCUUAUAAGACAUUUGAAGUGGUGUUUAUUGUCCUGGUGGCUGGAUCCCUCAGUUUGGUGACCAUUAUCGGGAACAUCCUAGUCAUGGUUUCCAUUAAAGUCAACCGCCACCUCCAGACCGUCAACAAUUACUUUUUAUUCAGCUUGGCCUGUGCUGACCUUAUCAUAGGUGUUUUCUCCAUGAACUUGUACACCCUCUACACUGUGAUUGGUUACUGGCCUUUGGGACCUGUGGUGUGUGACCUUUGGCUAGCCCUGGACUAUGUGGUCAGCAAUGCCUCAGUUAUGAAUCUGCUCAUCAUCAGCUUUGACAGGUACUUCUGUGUCACAAAACCUCUGACCUACCCAGUCAAGCGGACCACAAAAAUGGCAGGUAUGAUGAUUGCAGCUGCCUGGGUCCUCUCUUUCAUCCUCUGGGCUCCAGCCAUUCUCUUCUGGCAGUUCAUUGUAGGGGUGAGAACUGUGGAGGAUGGGGAGUGCUACAUUCAGUUUUUUUCCAAUGCUGCUGUCACCUUUGGUACGGCUAUUGCAGCCUUCUAUUUGCCAGUGAUCAUCAUGACUGUGCUAUAUUGGCACAUAUCCCGAGCCAGCAAGAGCAGGAUAAAGAAGGACAAGAAGGAGCCUGUUGCCAACCAAGACCCCGUUUCUCCAAGUCUGGUACAAGGAAGGAUAGUGAAGCCAAACAAUAACAACAUGCCCAGCAGUGACGAUGGCCUGGAGCACAACAAAAUCCAGAAUGGCAAAGCCCCCAGGGAUCCUGUGACUGAAAACUGUGUUCAGGGAGAGGAGAAGGAGAGCUCCAAUGACUCCACCUCAGUCAGUGCUGUUGCCUCUAAUAUGAGAGAUGAUGAAAUAACCCAGGAUGAAAACACAGUUUCCACUUCCCUGGGCCAUUCCAAAGAUGAGAACUCUAAGCAAACAUGCAUCAGAAUUGGCACCAAGACCCCAAAAAGUGACUCAUGUACCCCAACUAAUACCACCGUGGAGGUAGUGGGGUCUUCAGGUCAGAAUGGAGAUGAAAAGCAGAAUAUUGUAGCCCGCAAGAUUGUGAAGAUGACUAAGCAGCCUGCAAAAAAGAAGCCUCCUCCUUCCCGGGAAAAGAAAGUCACCAGGACAAUCUUGGCUAUUCUGUUGGCUUUCAUCAUCACUUGGGCCCCAUACAAUGUCAUGGUGCUCAUUAACACCUUUUGUGCACCUUGCAUCCCCAACACUGUGUGGACAAUUGGUUACUGGCUUUGUUACAUCAACAGCACUAUCAACCCUGCCUGCUAUGCACUUUGCAAUGCCACCUUCAAGAAGACCUUUAAACACCUUCUCAUGUGUCAUUAUAAGAACAUAGGCGCUACAAGGUAAAAUAUCUUUGAAAAAGAUAGAAGGUGGGCAAGGGGAGCUUGAGAAGAAUAAAAGGGAUAAACGAGCUCCUAGUUUUAAAAUCUCUGCCAUUGCACUUUAUAGUCUGAUUACAAAACGUGCAAUUCAGGAGCCCAGCAGUGACACACUUAUCACGCCUAGGCUCCAGUUUGCAAAAAUUGCACCUUAUAAACUGUCAGUAUUAGGAGCAAUGAGACAAUGAAAGAAACAUGUUGGGAUCGUGGAUUUAAGAAACUAUACACUGUUUCUCAUAAUCUCUUGAAGAAGGGCUUCUGAUUCUACAAUUUUAUCAGUCUCUGCACAAGAGGAAUAACCUUGUUCCUUUUUUGUUACUUUUGUUGUUGUUGUUCUCAUGUGUCCUUAAGAGAAGGAAAUGCCACAGUUACAAGGUAAACAUGGAGACUUAAACAUAAAGAAAUAGGCACUAUACAAUGGGGACAUAAAAAAAGAAAAUCAAAGAAGGAUGCAGAAAUUGUCUCCGGAGUGUUAAGCAUAUUUUAUUCUUUUGUUACGGUCCUAUUUAGAGGAUUGGAAUGUAAUAAAUGCUUAUUUUUUGCCUUUCUUUUUCCCACCAUGAAGAGAAAGCAAACAAACAGAAACCCCAACUAGGUCACACCAUUUUUCUUCUUGUUAUGCCACUAUUUUGUACAUCCCUGUUCUAUAUUGUUUAUAGGGAAAACCUACAGGACUUUCACUAAAGCUAGCCAGAGACAGCCAUGAAAAUGGACGUUUCACCCCUCCUCACUGUGUCCUUUGCAUUCGUUGGGGAUAUCAAGGUCUAUAAGGAUUUAGUGCACUUAUAAUCCUAUAUGCGAAAUGUUUAAACCAAUCUGAUUUUCUCCUAAAUAGCCUUUUAUAUCAACAGAAUAUCCUACCUAAAACAUAAACCUGUUUAAGAAACCAUCGUCACUGUAAAGUUGAGGUUUCAUCAAAUUAAAUAAUGGACUAUCUAGUUGGACCAAGUUUAUUAAAGUCAGGUGAAUUUUAAGAUUAAAAAAUAGAAGUUUAGGACUUUCUAUUUCAACCUGAAUUUGCCUGACCCAUGUAUGAAAUGUUAACUUAUAGAAAAUGAACUCCUGACUUUCUCAGCAGAAAGGAAUGCUGUUUUAUUUAUUUGGAAUCCUAAACAGGAUUAACAUACUCACAUAGCACCAGUGAUUUCUGGGCCAGUCCCUAGAGAAUAGAACCUUCUAUCCAAUGCCUGCUAAAGGAUGAUAUUCAAAUUAUAACCAAGUGAGGAUGUCUGCAAUUAUCCUAUGACCCCAUGAAAGGGGAAAAAACGAUAUUUUAAAAACUAUUACUGAAACAAUUACAUAUUCCAUAUUCCUCAAAUUGUCAAUUCUCCCUAACAUUAUUUAACUUCAAAAUUCUCUUAUCAAUAGAAUUAUAGUAAUCUUUGUGACAGAAAUGUAGUGGCUAACUAAAUAGAGGCCAAACGAGCUUACAGAAUCUGACAGAAGGAGGUAGGUGGCUGUUGCCAUGCCACAUCUCACCAUCUAAUUCUAGACCAUAAUAAUCAUGUCAGGAACUAUUAUCUAAGUGGUGGCAUUAUAUAGAAUCUUGCCACGUAGAGAUUUUUUAUUUGGUCGUCUAAAUAAAUAUAGGAUUAGGAUUAUACGGAUUCACAUACAACUAGUUAUUUUUAUCCUUUAUAUUUUUCUUACAGUAUUUGCUGUAGUUUUCCAAUGAGAUUUUCUAAAAAUGGCUCAAUCAAUGGAAAUCAAAUUAUAAACGCAUUUGCAAAUUUCAUAUUUUGGAUUUUAGAUUUAUGAUAUCUUGUUCAGUAAUAAUAAUGUUAGUUACAUGGUAAAUUUAUCAAUAUUAGACCCCAGCACUUAAAAGAAUUAUUUUGUAUGAUUAGCCUCAUAGAUGCCACCUCAACAUUUUGGAGAGUUAAGGAGGAAAAAAAGCAUGAGGGAAAAAAAAAACCAAAAAACUUAUAAGUUAGUAAGAAGCAAAUUGCCAGCAGUAUUUAUAUUUGACUUAUCCUUCGUAAAAACAAUUUCCUGUUUAAAUAACUUCAGUCAUUACCCCCCCAAAGUAAUCUUCCAUAUUUAAAGCAUUCAUUUAUAGAGAUUCCCUUACCUACAGUUACUUCAACAUGCACUUUUACAUUUUAAAUUCAUAUUUAUUUUCAUAUUGUUUCUUCAAAUGAAGGAAUCAGUUGAACGGAAAUAACGUCAAGCCAGUGGGCUCCUCGAGUUUCUGAAAACCAGAGAAUUGACUAGCCAAGUAUUUCCCUUUUUAAUGUAUUGUAUUAUUAUUAUGUAGAUUUGGCUUCAGUUGGGAAGAACCCUUUGGCAUCCAGGAUUCAGGAUUCAGGGUCUUUUUUUGUUUGCUCUAAUAAUCCAACGCACCAUGAAUCAAGCUUUUAGUCUCUGCUGCCAUUGUAUCCUUCCUUUUCCUCCCUCUGUUAUUGAUCCUUGCCACAGCCACUGCAACCUCAUUGAAAGAGAAACUGUCACUUUAAAGAAAGAAAUUGAAGAUAGGCUGACACCAUGGAAACUACGUCAAACAGAUAAGAAAAAUGGAAGGAAUACUGAAAAUGAUAGAUGAUUGGAGAGAUAUGGAGAUUAUAUUCAAGGAUUUUUAUUAACCACUGCUGGAUUUGUCUAUUUCAGUGGCUCUCAAACAGAGACAAUUCCCCUCUCCCCGAAAGGGGACACUUAGCAAUGUGUAAAGACAUUUUUGGUUGCCACACUGGGAGGAAUGCUAUUGGUAUCUAGUGCAUAGAGGCUGGGAAUGCUGCUAAAUAGCCUAUAAUGCUCAGGACAUUUUCCCCCAACCCCUUUAAACAAAUAUUAUUUGGCUCAAAAUGUCAAUAGUUCCAAGAUUGAGAAAUUCUUGUCUACUUUAAGGGAUUUCUAAAGCUUGCCUCUUAUUAGUGGGAAAAUAACCCUGCAUUAUUUUUAGAAUAUCAAUGCAAAUUCCUCACCUGUUAGAAAAAGGUAAUACUCACCAACCAUGUAUCAGAAAAACUUUUCUCCUGAGUCUGGUGUAUGUGUCAGUCACAGAUUGGGAACUCAGGCCACAUCUACAUAUCAAAAAUCACCAGACUAUGCAUAUCGCACAUCUUUUUUCCAGCAUCUUAAUGUUCAAUUAUGAUUGCCACAGAUCUAGUCAAUUGAGGUUGCAGUAGUUGGCCAUCAAAAUAUUUGCAGUUGAUAUGAUCAGUUUCUACUGGAGCUGCAAUUUUUCCUUUCAAAAAAUAUUAAGAGCCUCUUUCAGAAACAAUAUCAUUUAUCUUCUUUGCAUUUACUGGAAAGGUGUAUCUGUAAGGUCUUUGUUUUUUCUCUCCUCAUAGCAAUAAUGUAGCUAUCCCAGAGUGAUAUUAUAAGAAGAGGAGAUUAAGAAUAUGGAAAAAGUCUGUUCAUUUCUUCGAAACAAGAAAUGAUUUUCCUUUUACCAGUUCAUCAUUAAUUUAACGCCAGCUCCCAAGUAUUAGGGCAGAGUAAUCAAUAUGAGAAGCCACAACGGGUAAGCUUUCUGAUUUGAAAUGUACAAGCUGGAUGUCCAACAUACUCCUGCUCUUUGUUCAUUUGCUUUUUUGAUCCUGAAGAUCUGACAUUGGGAGAGAUGGGAAUUCAAAAUGAUGGCAACAAUUACUCAGCAAUGCAGUCUGUUUUUAUUUUCUCCUACUUAGUUCAUUGACAGUUUCCUCCUCGCCCCAGUUUGAUAAUAUCCCUUUCAACAACCAUAGUACCGGUGUUGCAAAUAGUUUAGGAAAGCACCCAAAGCUGGAUGAAAUUGUGCAAAGUGUAUUCUCAGCAUGUAUAUUCAAUACCAUGCCUCUUAAAAAUGCUUCUCUUAAAGGGUGCACGCUGUAGCAUGAAAUGUGUGCAUAUUUAAUGUAUCUUCCUGGAAUAUGCUAUGUGCUAAAUAUAUAUAUAUUCUAUAAAUAAAAUAAUAAAAUGUACAAUAGAAAUACA